CUACUCAAAGCAACUGCUGUCUUUCAGACAUAUUGAGAAACAUCAGGUUACCUUUUUUAAAUAAACAUAUCAUUGAAGCAUAACACAGAGAGAAAAUGAAUAAGUCAUAAGUGUAUAGCUCAGUGAACUUCCACAGAGAACAUAUCUGCGUAACCAGCACCCAGAUCAAAAGACAGAAUCUUACCAGUGCCCAGACGCACCCCACACCAUGCUCUAUUCCAGUGUGACCCACCCAAGCAUACCCACUACUCAGGUGGCCUUUUGAAAGAGGAGAGGGCAUGACUGUGACAAAGCAGAAGGGUGGCUAACACCAGCACUGCCACUUAGAGGGGUGCCCAGGUAGAGGGGAAACAGGGAAGAGAGCAGAGGCCAUGAGGUAAAGAAAAGCUUCAUGUGAGUGUGGAAGAGAACGACCCAGUGAGCGUGGCAGGACCCUCGCCAACUGUGACUGGAAGCUGCAUGUAGAACUUGAAGCAAUCACCUAGGAACUUGUCGUCAUGGUAAUGGAUUCAGAUGCUUUAUCAGUUUGGAACUCGGCUGCAAUAUCAGUUUGGAACUCGAACCAUUUCUAGACUCUACGCCCAAAGGAAGACAGACUUUUGAGUGGAAGCGAUACAAAUUACCUGUGGAGCAGAAAACAAAGAUCUCCUGUUGGCACUCAGGCUUCCUCCUGCUCUAGGUGACACGUGCACCAUGGCCGGCUACGCCCGCUUGAAGAAUGUCCUUCUGGCACUCCAGACCCGUCUGCAGCCACUCCAAGAAGGAGACAGCAGACAAGACCCUGCCUCCCAGAAGCGCCUCCUGGUGGAAUCUCUGUUCAGGGACUUAGAUGCAGAUGGCAAUGGCCACCUCAGCAGCUCCGAACUGGCUCAGCAUGUGCUGAAGAAGCAGGACCUGGAUGAAGACUUACUUGGUUGCUCACCAGGUGACCUCCUCCGAUUUGACGAUUACAACAGUGACAGCUCCCUGACCCUCCGCGAGUUCUACAUGGCCUUCCAAGUGGUUCAGCUCAGCCUCGCCCCCGAGGACAGGGUCAGUGUGACCACAGUGACCGUGGGGCUGAGCACAGUGCUGACCUGCGCCGUCCAUGGAGACCUGAGGCCACCAAUCAUCUGGAAGCGCAACGGGCUCACCCUGAACUUCCUGGACUUGGAAGACAUCAAUGACUUUGGAGAGGAUGAUUCCCUGUACAUCACCAAGGUGACCACCAUCCACAUGGGCAAUUACACCUGCCAUGCUUCCGGCCACGAGCAGCUGUUCCAGACCCACGUCCUGCAGGUGAAUGUGCCGCCAGUCAUCCGUGUCUAUCCAGAGAGCCAGGCACAGGAGCCUGGAGUGGCAGCCAGCCUAAGAUGCCAUGCUGAGGGCAUUCCCAUGCCCAGAAUCACUUGGCUGAAAAACGGCGUGGAUGUCUCAACUCAGAUGUCCAAACAGCUCUCCCUUUUAGCCAAUGGGAGCGAACUCCACAUCAGCAGUGUUCGGUAUGAAGACACAGGGGCAUACACCUGCAUUGCCAAAAAUGAAGUGGGUGUGGAUGAAGAUAUCUCCUCGCUCUUCAUUGAAGACUCAGCUAGAAAGACCCUUGCAAACAUCCUGUGGCGAGAGGAAGGCCUCAGCGUGGGAAACAUGUUCUAUGUCUUCUCCGACGACGGUAUCAUCGUCAUCCAUCCUGUGGACUGUGAGAUCCAGAGGCACCUCAAACCCACGGAAAAGAUUUUCAUGAGCUAUGAAGAAAUCUGUCCUCAAAGAGAAAAAAAUGCAACCCAGCCCUGCCAGUGGGUAUCUGCAGUCAAUGUCCGGAACCGGUACAUCUAUGUGGCCCAGCCAGCACUGAGCAGAGUCCUUGUGGUCGACAUCCAAGCCCAGAAAGUCCUACAGUCCAUAGGUGUGGACCCUCUGCCGGCUAAGCUGUCCUAUGACAAGUCACAUGACCAAGUGUGGGUCCUGAGCUGGGGGGACGUGCACAAGUCCCGACCAAGUCUCCAGGUGAUCACAGAAGCCAGCACCGGCCAGAGCCAGCACCUCAUCCGCACACCCUUUGCAGGAGUGGAUGAUUUCUUCAUUCCCCCAACAAACCUCAUCAUCAACCACAUCAGGUUUGGCUUCAUCUUCAACAAGUCUGAUCCUGCAGUCCACAAGGUGGACCUGGAAACAAUGAUGCCCCUCAAGACCAUCGGCCUGCACCACCAUGGCUGCGUGCCCCAGGCCAUGGCACACACCCACCUGGGCGGCUACUUCUUCAUCCAGUGCCGACAGGACAGCCCCGCCUCUGCUGCCCGACAGCUGCUCGUUGACAGUGUCACAGACUCUGUGCUUGGCCCCAAUGGUGAUGUAACAGGCACCCCACACACAUCCCCCGACGGGCGCUUCAUAGUCAGUGCUGCAGCUGACAGCCCCUGGCUGCACGUGCAGGAGAUCACAGUGCGGGGCGAGAUCCAGACCCUGUAUGACCUGCAAAUAAACUCGGGCAUCUCAGACUUGGCCUUCCAGCGCUCCUUCACUGAAAGCAAUCAAUACAACAUCUACGCGGCUCUGCACACGGAGCCGGACCUGCUGUUCCUGGAGCUGUCCACGGGGAAGGUGGGCAUGCUGAAGAACUUAAAGGAGCCACCCGCAGGGCCAGCUCAGCCCUGGGGGGGUACCCACAGAAUCAUGAGGGACAGUGGGCUGUUUGGACAGUACCUCCUCACACCAGCCCGAGAGUCACUGUUCCUCAUCAAUGGGAGACAAAACACGCUGCGGUGUGAGGUGUCAGGUAUAAAGGGGGGGACCACAGUGGUGUGGGUGGGUGAGGUAUGAAGGGCCCAGAGCAGAGCCCUGGGCCAAGGAACACCCCCUAGUCCUGACACUGCAGCCUCAAGCAGGUACGCUGUACAUUUUUACAGACAAAAGCAAAAACCUGUACUCGCUUUGUGGUUCAACACUGGUCUCCUUGCAAGUUUCCUAGUAUAAGGUAUGCGCUGCUACCAAGAUUGGGGUUUUUUCGUUAGGAAGUAUGAUUUAUGCCUUGAGCUACGAUGAGAACAUAUGCUGCUGUGUAAAGGGAUCAUUUCUGUGCCAAGCUGCACACCGAGUGACCUGGGGACAUCAUGGAACCAAGGGAUCCUGCUCUCCAAGCAGACACCUCUGUCAGUUGCCUUCACAUAGUCAUUGUCCCUUACUGCCAGACCCAGCCAGACUUUGCCCUGACGGAGUGGCCCGGAAGCAGAGGCCGACCAGGAGCAGGGGCCUCCCUCCCGAACUGAAAGCCCAUCCGUCCUCGCGUGGGACCGCAUCUUCUCCCUCGCAGCUGCUUCUUGCUUUUCUUUCCAUUUGACUUGCUGUAAGCCUGAGGGAGAGCCAACAAGACUUACUGCAUCUUGGGGGAUGGGGAAAUCACUCACUUUAUUUUGGAAAUUUUUGAUUAAAAAAAAAUUUUAUAAUCUCAAAUGCUAGUAAGCAGAAAGAUGCUCUCCGAGGUCCAACUAUAUCCUUCCCUGCCUUAGGCCGAGUCUCGGGGGUGGUCACAACCCCACAUCCCACAGCCAGAAAGAACAAUGGUCAUCUGAGAAUACUGGCCCUGUCGACUAUUGCCACCCUGCUUCUCCAAGAGCAGACCAGGCCACCUCAUCCGUAAGGACUCGGUUCUGUGUUGGGACCCCAAAAAACCAGAACAAGUUCUGUGUGCCUCCUUUCAGCACAGAAGGGAGACAUCUCAUUAGUCAGGUCUGGUACCCCAGAUUCAGGGCAGACUGGGCUUGCCUGGCAAGGUAUGGGUGGCCUCCAGGCUCAAUGCAGAAACCCCAAGGACACGAGUGGGGCCAGGUGAGUUCCUGAAGCUAUACCUUUUCAAAACAGAUUUUGUUUUCCUACCUGUGGCCCAUCCACUCCUCUCUGGUACCCCAUCCCCGCAUCAGCACUGCAGAGAGAACACAUUUCGGCGAGGGUUUUCUUACCCACAUUCCCCAAUCAAUACACACACACUGCAGAACCCAGAACAGAAGGCCACAGGCUGGCACUACUGCAUUCUCCUUAUGUGUCUCAGGCUGUGGUGACUCUCACAUGGGCAUCGAAGAAGUACAACCCACAUAGCCCUCUGGAGACCGCCUAGAUCAGAGACUCAGCAAAAACAGGCUCGCCUUCCCUCUCCCACAUAUGAGUGGAACUUACAUGUGUCCUGGUUUGAAUGAUCAUUUUGCAAGCCACACGGGUUGGGAGAGGUGGUCUCACCACAGACGUCUUUGCUAAUUUGGCCACCUUCACCUACUGACAUGACCAGGAUUUUCCUUUGCCAUUAAGGAAUGAACUCUUUCAAGGAGAGGAAACCCUAGACUCUGUGUCACUCUCAACACACACAGCUCCUUUCACUCCUGCCUGACUGCCAAGCCACCUGCAUCCCCCGCCCCAGAUCUCAUGAGAUCAAUCACUUGUAUGUCUCACGCAACUUGGUCCACCAAACGCCUGUCCCCUGUAACUCCUAGGGGUGCGCCUAGACAGGUACGUCUGUUUUUUAUUUUAAAAGAUAUGCUAUGUAGAUAUAAGUUGAGGAAGCUCACCUCAAAAGCCUAGAAUGCAGUUUCACAGUAGCUGGGAUGCAUGGAUGACCCAUCUCACCCCUUUUUUUUUCCUGCCUCAAUAUCUUGAUAUGUUAUGUUUACUCCCAAUCUCCCAUUUUUACCACUAAAAUUCUCCAACUUUCAUAAACUUUUUUUUGGAAAAAUUUCCAUUGUAUCAGCCCCUGACAGAAAAAGGAUCUCUGAGCCUAAAGGAGGAAAAGUCCCACCAACUACCAGACCAGAACACGAGCCCCUCUGGGCAGCAGGAUUCCUAAGUCAAAGACCAGUUUGACCCAAACUGGCCUUUUAAAAUAAUCAGGAGUGACAGAGUCAACUUCUGCAGCACCUGCUUCUCCCCCACUGUCCCUUCCAUCUUGGAAUGUGUCUAAAAAAGCAUAGCUGCCCUUUGCUGUCCUCAGAGUGCAUUUCCUGGAGACGGCAGGCUUAGGUCUCACUGACAGCAUGCCAGACACAACUGAAUCGAAGCAGGCCUGAAGCCUAGGUCAGGGUUUCAGGAGUCCAGCCCCAGGAGGCAAAGUCACCAAUGCAGGGAGGUAAAUGCCUUUUGGCAGGAAAACCAAUAGAGUUGGUUGGGUGGGGAGUCAGGGGUGGGAGGAGAAGGAGGAAGAGGAGGAAGGCCAGACUGGCCUGCCCUUUCUCCCAUACUUCACCCCAGCAGAGGUUCAUGGGACACAGUUGGAAAGCCACUGGGAGGAAAUGCCUCACUACAGGGGGGCCUCCUGUAGCAAGCCCAGCCGGUAAUCCUCCUAAUGAACCCACAAGGUCAAUUCACAACUGAUAUCUUAGCUAUUAAAGAAGUACUGACUUUACCAAAAGAAUCAUCAAGAAAGCUAUUUAUAUAAACCCCCUCAGUCAUUUUGAAAUAAAAUUAAUUUUACAAAAA